AUGUGCUUGUCCUCGGGACACAUUAGGAAUGAACCCAGGCCUCAGUCCUGGCCUCCUCCUCAAGGCUGGGUGCUCAGACGUCCCCCUCAGCCCCUUUCUCUAGACCUUCCGGCUGAACAAACGAGAACAUCUCACAGCCCUGCAACAGCCAGGAGCUGCUCGUGGAGCUCCACGCCCGGCUGGAGAGAGAGGAGGCACCCUGGGCAGCCCGCCAGCACCCAGGCUCUCACAGUGGAAGCCCACGUCUUCUUGGGCUCUAUUUUGAAAGCUGUUCUUUCCACGACGGCUUUGACAAGAAUCGAUUUGAGUGAGCCGGCGUGUCAAUACAGGCCAGCACAGGACUGGCCUCAGGGCCACAUUGGGGAGGGUGGCGACCAGGCCCUGGCUGCAGCCCACGUGGGCAAAAGCAUGGCCAGGCAGGAGGUGGGGCCUGUGAGCUUGGCUACAGCGACCGUGGGCGCUGGGCCCGGGGCUCCUCAGCCCUGAGGGGAGACCCAGGCCCAGGCAGGCUCCCAGGCGGGCUCCCGGGCUCCCAGCCUUCCGAUCUUCUCCCUUUGAGACCUUGCCUUCUGCACAGUGACAGGAAAGAGCCCUGAGUCCCACUUUGCAGGGAUGUAUUGCAUUUCCAGAAAGUUCCUUCCGGGUGCAGAGUGAUACAUGAACCCUGGGGACUCACUCCAACUUGGUAUUGAUUUUCUCCACGGAGGACCCAGCAGUCACGGCCCGUGUCUGCACAGCCCCUUGGAUCCUGCGGAGGAAUUCAGCCGGCCCCUCCCCCUGUGCCGAAAACCACGGAGGCAAAGCCAGGCCAGGUUCAGGUUCCACGCAAAGCGCCCUCCUGUAGCCAAGCCCAGCCCCAUGAGGGUACAGUGAGAACACGGGAGAGGACUGAGAGACCGCUGGCUGCCGAGGGAGGAAGAGCAGGAUUCGCACCCCCGUCAUCGCUGGGCCCACACGCCGCCGACAGCUUCCGCGUGUGGCCAUCUGUCUUUCAGAAACCCUCUGGCAGAGGGACCCAGCAGAUGACACGGGGGCCGUUCACACUCUGAAACCUGCCUGGAGUCAAAACACUGCUGGCGAGCCUCCACCGCAAACCCAAUCCAGAUGGUCUUCCCUGGUGGCCCUCGGGGUGGCGGGCACCCUGCCCACUCCCUGCCAGCCCCUGCCCGCUGGACUCCAGGCCCGGCCGAGCCCCCGACCGGUCUCCUGACCCAGCAUGCUGCUCUCCCCUGGGCCCGGCUUUCUCGCCCGCUGGGACUCCCAGGCCCCUCCAGCCCAGCCCCGAGAGCAGGAGCCCCAAGGGAGGCUUGGCGGCUGUGGAGGCGAGUGGGCCACGUGUAGCUGGGAGGCCGGCAGGACCAGGAGCCCCUCACAGCGCAGCACCCACAGCAUCACGAGCCACUUCCACUCCUGGGUGGCCUGGGGGCCCCCACCCUGCUCUGAGCUGCCCCUUGUUGUGACCUGGGGUCCCCCGUGGUGGGCCCGCCCCUUGAGCCUGGGAUCCAGCCUCAGCGAGGCUCCAGAAGUGUCGUCUCCGCCGGCCAGGCGUCAGCGCCUCCACCCAGGAUCACACACUCCUAUCUCUGCACUUCUGCCCUCCAUCCUGCUCCACGCCGCCUCUGCUUGUUAUUCCAGCACAUUCCAGGGUGAUGCCUGCUGAAGCCACGCAGCCAGUGCCUCCACCCUACCCCCCAUCUGACCCACCGGCCCCUUCCGCACGCUGGAAGCCUGCCCGGCCUGAAGUGUCCUCACCUGUCGCCCUAUCCUCCCCUCCACUCCAGCCCACCGGUGACUCAGCCCUCACAGCUCUCUCCUCCCCGAGGGAGCCGGUGACUUGGCUCUGAUGGUGCCGGGACCCAGCCCCGGCAUGUUCAGAAUCCUUGUCCUUUAACCUGCGUCCACAUGUAGUCGCCUCCACCUCCCUGCCUGAACCUCCAGGCCCUGCAGAGCAAACACUGCUGCCUGCAGGAGACCCCUGGGGCCUUCUCCGUCCCCUCAUCCUCCUAAGGAGCCUCCCCUGCCACCGUGCCAGAAUGUGCCGGAGGAACAGAGGCCCGAGCCUCCCGUGGCCCCAGCGAGGCUUCCUCUGGGGAAGACAGUGAGCCCAACGCCCUGGCUCUCGAGGGGUGGACGGAGUCCAGCUGGCAUCGACCGGGUGCCCCUCUUCACCGGUGUCCACAGUCCUUGAGAGCAAAGGUGGUCCCAGCAGUGGAGCAGAGGGCAAGGGUGGGGCAUGUAGAGUCUCCAGGGAGCCACUGUUGGUUAGAGAGGGAGCCCGAAGUGGGCUCCGGACCCCAGCAGGGACAGCGUCCCCUUCCAGCGGGGGCAGCCGAUUGAUCUGGGCACACGAGCAGGAGGAGCGGCGCCACCCAGGGCUGACCUCACGGCCCUGCUCACGUCUCGGGGCAUUUUGGCAGACCCACCUAGACCUGGGGGACAGCCUGAUUUCCUGCAGCCAUGACCUACAAGGGUGGCAGCUCUCUCAGGCUUGAGUAACCAGGACACAGACCUGGGCCAUUUAAUGCGCAGGCAGCCCCAAGUCCCGGCAGGGCCAGAAGCAGAGACGGCGGCUGGGGAUGAAAGUGCACGCUGGUCCCAGAUGGGGCUGGGGGUGAAAGCUGCAUGCUGAUCCCUGGGCCCCCUCACUCUAUGAGCUCCUGAAAGGAGGGAAGCCCCCACACCCUACUGAGUGGAGUGCUCCUUGGCCUGGGACCCCGUCCAGUGUCUGCUGCUGUGGGGGCGGGCUCUGGGCAGAGAGAGGCCAGACAGGCACCCAGGAAAGCUGGAACACAUCCCUCCUGCUUCCCCCAGGGUUCCCAGAGGCGACCUCCCUCCUGCACAGGCAUUUGUCAUCCUUACCCUCUAGGACAGCUUUGCCAUGUGCAGUGAACCCCUGGACAGUGUUGCGUGCCACUUUGCCGGAUUUGGACUGUAUACAGACCGAAGCAUGUGGCAUGAAGCCUUCUGCUGUCAGCAAGUUCCUUGUCCCUCGACAGUAUGUGCCCAGGCUGCCCUUCAAGGUGGCAGUGAUGGCAGUUGUCUCUUGCACGCUGCGUACAGUUCUGUCACUGACUCUUACACACAGCCCUGGAGACGGGAGAGUGCCGGGAGCAUUCUAUGCAAGUGUCCUGGCCUUUGCGGGCGUCUCCACAGCACAAACACGAGUCAGGGACCACCCCUCUUCUGCUUCCAUGAUUCCACCAACUGGGUGGGGCAGAGCAGUGCCAGGGCCGGAGGCACGCCCCAGGUGAGGGCAGGUGGCCAUGCCAGUGAGUGCACUGCGUUCUCAGUUAAUUCAUCCGAAAUAUUUCUAAGUUUCUUGAUUAUUGCAGUUGCAUCCCCAAGAUAAUGCCGCCCUCACCAAGUAGAAGGCACAUGUGCUCUGAUGGCCCCUCCCACACUGGGGUCAGGGCACAGCAACUUAGCGAGGCGACGUGGGGGCUCAGAGGACCUCGGACCAGGCUCGGCACAUGGGGCUUCUCCAGCCAGCCAGGGGGAAGCACCCUGCAGACUGCUAACUUUUGCAAAAUAGAGUAAAAAAGAUCAGCUAGAAAAAUAAAACAAAAAAGGAAAGAUA